AGCAUAAAGUUGGGAGUGACACCAGAGCCUUCUGCAAGAUGCUUCUGAUUCUGCUGUCAGUGGCCCUGCUGGCCUUCAGCUCAGCUCAGGACUUAGAUGAAGAUGUCAGCCAAGAAGACGUUCCCUUGGUAAUAUCAGAUGGAGGAGACUCUGAGCAGUUCAUAGAUGAGGAGCGUCAGGGACCACCUUUGGGAGGACAGCAAUCUCAACCCUCUGCUGGUGAUGGGAACCAGAAUGAUGGCCCUCAGCAGGGACCACCCCAACAAGGAGGCCAGCAGCAACAAGGUCCACCACCUCCUCAGGGAAAGCCACAAGGACCACCCCAACAGGGAGGCCAUCCCCCUCCUCCUCAAGGAAGGCCACAAGGACCACCCCAACAGGGAGGCCAUCCCCGUCCUCCUCGAGGAAGGCCACAAGGACCACCCCAACAGGGAGGCCAUCAGCAAGGUCCUCCCCCACCUCCUCCUGGAAAGCCCCAGGGACCACCUCCCCAAGGGGGCCGCCCACAAGGACCUCCACAGGGGCAGUCUCCUCAGUAAUCUAGGAUUCAAUGAUAGGAAGUGAAUAAGAAGAUGACAGUGUUUCAAAUGCCUUGAAACAUAAUGUGAUCAUGCUCUAACUUCAAUAUACCAAUAAAAUAAUCAGCUUGCAAUUUCUGAUUAUAGCAUCUCCUUCUGAGUGUUUGGGACUCUGGAAUCUGAGACCCAUGUUCACAUUGUAAGAACAUCCAGGACCCCUUCUCCUUGAUGUUUCCAGCAAGCUUCUUUCCUCCUUAUCCUUAUUAAGUCAUCUGCCUGGGGAAGGAGUUCCACUGUUUCUUUCCUUCUCUGUCUUCUUAGCUCGAAUUUAAAUUGCACAAUUAUUUUCAGGUCAUUUCCUGAUAGUCUAGUCAGCUUAUGAAUGUAAGCAAAACAGGACCAAUGAAAGAAAGUCCCAGAAGCUGAGAGAAACUUUAACAAGUUUGAGAGUAACUUAUUUUGUUUUCUAGGAAAGUGAGUAUGGUUCUAUGCCUGUAUUCCCCAGAAGCCACUAGACCUAUUUUCCCCUAUUUUAUCACUGAUCAGUUCUGUCCCUGCCUAUGAUUCUUACCAUUCUUAAGAAAACCUGAAUGGAUUUCAUCAAGGCGGCAGCAUAAUUUGAAGGGCAAUUGCGUGUGAAAAUUGAUGUGACUUGAUUUACACAAUAGUCAGAAAACAUUUUAGAAAUUGAUGACUUUAUAAUGCAACCAGGAGUAUUGAAAAAAAAGUAAGCAAUGAGCUCAAAUAAUUAAAAAAGAGAGACAAAAUACACUUGGGAGAACAGAAAUAAGAAUUAAUGAAAAUUUAAAAGAUUAAAUGAAUGAGAAGAAAUGAUUCAUAAAUUUUGAACUAACAGUAAUAACUUCUUGAAAAUCCAAUAAAAUUGGCAAAAGAUUGUGAAAAUUCUGGAAGAAUAAGGGAAACAGAUAAUCUUCAGAGUAAUCAGGUAAAGCUUAAACAAGUGUUUUAAAAGAUGAGUUUUUCCUACAUUCUGAAAAGCAAACAUGAAAAACUGAACACAGUUUUUACAGAUAUACAAUAUGGAGUGACUUAUAUACAAAAUGACCUUAAAAAUAUAUUAAACUCAUUAUAGUAGUUAAUAUCUAAGUAAAAUAUGAUGAAAUUUAAUAGAGAAUUCACUCCUCCCAAAAGCACCUUCAUGGAAGAUUCCUCAUUAACAGGCAGUCCUUUAGUAUGCUGAUUUAUACAAAAUGCUGAAAAGAAGAGAAAUACCCCAAGUUCUUGAAAAAAAAUUUUUUGAUAUGACUACUCUAACAGUAAUAACUAUAAAUCUCACUUUAAAUAAUUUAAAACAAAUUAAAGUGAUAUAUGAGUUAAAUGACCAAGCAGACUUGAUUCCAGGAAUGUUAAGGAAUGUUCAUUAUUUGUUUUGGAUAAUGAAGUCAGCAGAGGAAAAAAAAAUAUGACCAUCUCAAAAGAUGCCAACGUUGUCUUUGAUAAUAUUUAAUAUAUUUUUUAAAAAACAAUUCUUGUAAAAUACUUUUUUGAUUAGCCUUCUGACCAUGAUUAAAAUGGUGUACCUCAAAGUAGCUGCUAACCUUAUGUGUAUCUGCAACACCCUGAAAAAUUAUCUAAUAAAAAGGCACAAAGAAAAAGCUUGUCAAUGUUGUGGAUAAUUAGAAAGUGAAUAAUUUUAUUUAAUAUUAGAUAAACAAGCACAUAACAGAGAUACAUAUAUUCAAAUGGAAGGAGUAAAAUUACCACCACAUGCAGAUCUGUUUUUCUGUCCAGAAAAUAACAAGAGAUUCUACUCAGGUAAAAAAGGAAAGGAAGGAAAACCAUUGUAAUUAAAAUAAAAUUUAAUACAAUAGCCGUUUAUUAAUUCAACUUCUAAAGAAUCUUUGUGAUUACACAAUGACCAGCUAGUAAAUAUAAUAAGAAAAUGAUUAUUCACAAAGGAACCAAAAGGCCUAGUCUUCGAAUUUUUAAUGCCAUUGUGAUAGCAAGCAUCUGAUUAUUUUACUCUAAGUUAUUUCCACUUCUGAUUUUAAGAACAGCUUCUUUCCCAGGGAUGGGUUCCCCCUAGUGAUGUAUUCUCUUCACCACAAGAGUUUGCAGCUCUGGCUUUCUUUCUGCUCAUCUGUAAAGAUAACUACAGCUCCUCUAUAAACCAUCUCACCAUUAUUACCGAAAUCAGACAAAUUCUGGAGAUAGUCAAAGCUGUGAGGAUUCGAAGAUCUCUUUCACAUCUUGACCCAGUCAAUUCCGUUCACCAGUGUUAUGAAUCCAUUCCCCAAAAUUCCAAUUAGGAAUUAUAUAUUUAUUAUUAUAAUGAGGAUACUAUACAAGGCAUUUAGCAUGGCUGCAAAGAGAGAGCUCCAAUGUCUAAAUGCAACGCUGACAAUUUCUUCAUCUAUCACAUGUACCUGUUAUACAUACUUAUUAAUUGGAUGUGCAGUUAAUUUCUUCCUUUAAAAAAAAAACUAUAGGCUCAAUAUGAAAGUAGAAAGCACUAAGGUGUACUAAUGAAUGGGCACAUAGCUUUUUUCACAAAAAGAUUAUUUUGCCCCAGACAGCUAUCUGCAUUCUGAUCCAGAUACUGUAUGUUCUUAACAUAAAGUGAAAUUUCUCAUACUUCAUGAUGAAAGAAAAAACUGAAUUCUCAUUGUUAAUAAACAAAUAAAGACAAUUCUCUGCA